AAACGGCCCAGGCAUCCACCCAGCCGAGAGCACGAUGGCUACUGGGGAGCUCGGGGACUUGGGUGGCUACUACUUCAGGUUCUUGCCUCAGAAAACCUUCCAGUCUCUGAGCUCUAAGGAGAUCACCAGCCGGCUCCGCCAGUGGUCCAUGCUGGGCAGAAUCAAGGCGCAGGCGUUCGGCUUUGACCAGACCUUUCAGUCCUAUCGGAAGGAUGAUUUCGUUAUGGCUUUUUUCAAAGACCCAAAUGUUAUUCCCAAUUUGAAGUUACUUUCAGAUUCUUCUGGACAAUGGAUCAUAUUAGGAACUGAAGUGAAAAAAAUUGAAGCUAUAAAUGUUCCUUGCACACAGCUUUCAAUGUCAUUUUUUCAUCGGUUAUAUGAUGAAGAUAUUGUACGAGACAGUGGACAUAUUGUUAAAUGUUUAGAUUCUUUUUGUGAUCCAUUUCUCAUUUCUGAUGAGUUACGAAGAGUUUUGCUAGUGGAAGACUCAGAAAAAUAUGAAAUAUUCAGCCAACCAGAUAGAGAAGAGUUCCUGUUUUGUCUUUUCAAACAUCUUUGCCUUGGUGGAGCCCUUUGUCAAUAUGAGGAUGUGAUUAGCCCAUAUCUGGAAACAACAAAGCUUAUCUAUAAGGAUCUGGUGAGUGUUCGAAAGAAUCCUCAAACCAAGAAAAUACAGAUUACCUCUUCUGUCUUUAAAGUUUCAGCUUAUGAUUCUGCUGGUAUGUGCUAUCCUUCAGCAAAGAAUCAUGAACAGACAUUUUCUUACUUUAUUGUGGAUCCUAUCAGGCGUCACCUUCAUGUUUUAUACCACUGUUAUGGUGUGGGAGACAUGUCUUAAUGUUCUUUCAGAUUAUGUACCUCUACUAUUUUGUAUUUAUCAUUUUUCUAUCUUAAUACUAACUUAUAGAUAAACAUAUACUUUGCAAAUUAAUUCAAGAAAAAUGUAAGGAGCCUACUUAGAGCAGAAGAAAGCAAACACCAAGAUGCCUUUUUAAAAAUUUGUGUGGAAUACUAACCGGGGAUCAAAUUUCAUCCAUAAUAAAAUCUAUACCAAAAAAGUUGUGGAAUUUUUACAGAAAGUUACAAGGAAUUAGAAAUCUAGUUCAUAUUUGUUGCAUUGUGAUUCAAGUGAAUCCUCAAUUUUCCAUGUAUUUUAAUUUAUAAGCUAAUUAAUUAUGGAUUGAAAAUGUAGCAGAAAACUAAACAUGUCUACCACUGAUCAUUAAUAUGAAUUGUUAGUUUAUUUAACUUGUUUCAUUUAAUUACAUUUCUUCAUUGCACAAGCGUUUACAUCUGUAAAGCUAGGCAAAGCAUAACAAUUCUUUUGCUUCAUUUGUUCCACUUAUAAGCCUCAGUAAAGAAGUAACGUUCUGGGGCCUGGCACGGUGGCUCACGCCUGUAAUCUCAGCACUUUGGGAGGCCAAGGCGGGCGGAUCACGAGGUCAAGAGAUCGAGACCAUCCUGGCCAACAUGGUGAAACCCCGUCUCUACCAAAAGUACAAAAAUUAGCUGGCUGUGGUGGUGUGUGCCUGUAGUCCCAGCUACUCAGGAGGCUGAGGCAAGAGAAUCACUUGAACCCGGGAAGUGAGGUUGCAGUGAGCCGAGGCUGUGCCACUGUACUCUAGCUCUGGCAACAGAGCAAGACUCCGUCUCAGAAAAAAAAAAGGUUCUGAAAGUGGUUGUAAACUCUUGUAUCACAUAAUAAAUUAAAACUGCAGCUGUCCCACGGCUAAUACAAGAGCUACAUGUAAACAGAGAAAGUUGCCUGAUGGCAUUAGUAAGUCGUUCAAAGAGUGAGAAGCAGGUUAUCUUAGUACUGUUCCUUAUUUCAUUCAUAGAAUGAAUGUAUAACCUAGAUUGUUUUUGGUUUAUUUUGAUGGCAAAAAUCAUUGACAUAUAUCCCAUGGGUCAUGGGAAGCCUGUAAGAAAUGUUGAGGUUUGAGGAGGAGCAAGUUUGAAAGAUGUGUUUCUGUGUUGUGGGAUAAAGACGAUAAUCUUGGACUUGAACCUGGAUUUGAAUCUGGAAUGCAGCUGGCAAUUUGGGUAUAGAGCUCAGGAGAAAGAGUAUGUUUUACUUCUAAUACCUAACACAAUGACUUGGCAUAUUAAAUGUUUAUUGAAUGAAUAACUACUUUCUAGAUAUCCUCAUAAUACCCAUAGAUUUUUUUAAAUUACAUAAAAACAUAAAAUCAA